AGACCUGAUCCAAUGGCCGCUUGAUACAAUGGUGUCGUUCGGGAAACGCAGCCCUAACGUUGGUCCUAAGCUGACAAAUUGGUCUGUGGACGCCAAACUUCCGUGCUAGGACUUUCUGCGUGUGGACCGGGGGCCUAGUCCUGCGUGGGUCCAACACAGACAGGAGAAAGCUGCCUGCUUUUGUGCCUCCCGGAGGUCCUGGUAGAAGCGAAACGGGGACAGGAGCUGCAGCGUCCCAAGCCCAGUGAGGCGAAGCUACUGGAGACAGCUCUGCCGGGUCCAAAGUUGGGCUCACCGGCUGGAACUUGAAACCGGAGCACGCCGGACUCCUGCUGAAGCCAUCAUCUCUCUCUCCUGGCCCCGGGCGCCUUGGCCGGCGGGCACAACUGGUUUCGGGGCCAAGGUGGUCUGGAAGCCUGACUGUGGCGUCUGGCCUGGGCUCCCGCGAGCGGAAAAGGUUCCCCUCCUGUGAGAGGGAAACUAUGGAAGUUCCUACGCCCGGAGCCAGAACUCCUGCUGCUCCCGCCCGACCCAAGGUCUAGCUUGGCGGCCUCCCACCUGUGCUUCUGAGGGUUCUGCUUCCAAGAGGCUGCUGGUGCCCGGGACACCAGCAGUUUCGCCAUGGGUGUUUCGCCAUGGGAGUUUCGCCAUGGGUGACUUUGGCCUGAGAUGCGCUCCAUGGAGCAGAUUCUGGAGUUGCUGGUGUUGGAGGAGUUCCUGACUAUCCUGUCCCAGGACAUCCACAGCAGGGUGCAGAAGCUGCAACGGGCGAGCUGUGAAGAAGCUGUAACUCUUUUAAAGUAUAUGUAUGACUUUUAAAAGAGAGAGCUUGUGAAACUGAGGGAAUAGGUGAGUGAGAGAGAGGUUUUAUCUGCCAUCUUCCUCAAGGAGGCCCAGCCUCCCCUUUAUUCAUAGGGUUCUGGGUCUGGUGGGUCCAGAGGACUGAGACAUCUCGCUGUCUUAAUUCCCCAUUCAGAUUUUCUUGAUUGCCCUGAGUAGACCUUACACGGGCCAGUGAUUUUUUGUUGUUGUUGUUGUUGUUGUCUUCUCUGGAACCUUCAUCCUCCAGAUUUCCCCCCAGUGCAGUGAAGAGUGUGCUAUUGCUUUUGGUUUCCACGGGGAGGCAGUGUCGCUGUCAUAGUGUCCGCUCUGGAGGUAGAUCAAAGGGGGCUUUCAACUCCUGGCUCUGCUCCCUACUAGCUGUGCGACUUUGGGCAAGUGACUUUUGCUUGGCUGGGCUUCACUUUCUGCACUGGUCAAAUGCAGAAAGGGUAAUAGACCCUUCUGGGGUUGUUUGGAGGAUUAAAGGGAGAGCAGUAUGUCCGUAAUAAUCGCACUGCUGGCACACAGCUAGUGCUUGAAACUGUGAGCUGCUGUUAGGUUAGGGGCAGCAGUCUGGUCUCCUCUGCAGAGAUGGGUCUCAGUUAAUUGUGAACUUAAACAGUUUGGCACUGAGGCUUUGGGGUCAUUGCCCCAGGGCCACCCAAGUAAGCUUGUCUAAUUGAGAGGAACAGGAGCAGCUGGAGAAUGUGGGGGAGGAACCGAAGACCUAUGGGGGACAUGUGUGUACUGAAAUGGGCUUUCUCCCCACACCCUCCACACAAGCACAUACACACAUUCACUCUGGGUCAUGGCAUCAUAAAAACCUUGAGUUUAAACCAUCCCUUUCUCUUGUUGGGUCCAAAUGGACAGACUCUGGUUUUCUAUUGAAGAUUUACACGCAGAUUCCUGUCAUAAUUUUUCUUUUCUAUCGAGCCCUGUCAUGAUGAUAAGUGAUAGCAGGUUGGUUCCUAGAUCAUACACCAUGGACCUAGCACAGAAGUGUUUUCAGAAGAGCCUUUUCCUUACAAAACAGCAUGAAAGUCAUUGAGCCAAUGGAUACUGAGAUUUCAAACUGGAGCCAAUGGAUACUUAGAGGAGCCCUGAAGUGUAGAGUAGUUGCUACUUCUUGUUCACUAGGUCUAAUUAGCAUGUCAUCAGUGUAACAGACUAGUGUGUUGUCUUGUGAAAGAGAAAGGUGAUAAGAUCCCUGUGAACUAAACUAUGAUGUAGGGCUUGAAAAUUGAUAUACAAUACGCCUGAGGUAGGAUGGCGAAGGUGUAUUCCUGGUCUUACCAGCUGAAAGUAAAUUGCUUCUGGUGGUCUUUACUAACAGUUAUUGAGAAAAAAAGCAUUUUCAAGGUCAAGAGGUACAUACUAGGUUCCAGGGGAUAUGUUAAUUUGCUCAAGAAAUGAAACCACAUCUGGAACAGCAGCUGCAAUUGGAGUCAUCACCUGGCUUAGUUUACAAUGACCCACUACCAUCUUCCAAGAUCCAUCUGCCUUCUGCAUAGGCCAAACAGGUCCACAGAACUCGACCCUGGAAGAGAGAGUCGGGGUCAGGUCUUCGGGAGGUGGAGGGAUCGAAUGAGGGAACUGAUAUUCCAAGACUCCCCACAUCUUGGAGCUUCACUCGCCAGGCAUCCCGCGCUUUCCUGACGUCGCUUCCCCUAGUGGUGCAGCAGCGGAGAGCUUUGCUACCCAGAGCAGCAGGGAGGCGUGGCCACAGAGGCAGAGGCGUAGUCGAGCCGAGGAAGAGGAAAGUGGCCUCCGGGGAAGCCAGAGCUGACUGAAGUGCUCUUGGGAAGAACAAUUCAUUGAUUUGGUACCAACCUGAUGCACCCUGAUUUGUCAAAGGUGGUACCAGGUGGGUGUCAGUGUCACAUACAAGAGUAAAACUGUUCCUAGAGCAAAUGGCGAUGAGAGAGCUGAACGCGGAUUCAUGCUCAAGCCCCCAGAUGGGGGCUAUGUGGGAGACUAGUGGGUCUGUGAAAGAGAACUCCAGUCAGAGUAAGAAAUACAGCACAAAAAUAGAGAAUCUUGGUCCUGAGAGCGCUUGCAGGCACUUCUGGAGCUUCCGUUAUCAUGAAGCAACCGGACCGCUUGAGACUAUCAGCCAACUUCAGAAAUUGUGCCAUCAGUGGCUGAGGCCAGAGAUCCACUCAAAAGAGCAGAUCUUGGAAAUGCUGGUGUUAGAGCAGUUCCUGAGCAUUCUGCCCAAGGAGACCCAGAACUGGGUGCAGAAGCAUCAUCCACAGAAUGUCAAACAGGCUCUGGUCCUGGUGGAAUUCUUGCAGAGGGAGCCUGAUGGAACAAAGAAUGAGGUCACAGCCCAUGAGCUGGGAAAGGAGGCAGUGCUCUUGGGAGGAACAGCAGUGGCCCCAGGCUUCAAGUGGAAGCCAGCAGAGCCCCAACCAAUGGGUGUGUUCCAGAAAGAAUAUUGGAAUACAUACCGGGUACUACAAGAACAGCUGGGCUGGAACACUCACAAAGAAACCCAGCCUGUAUAUGAAAGAGCUGUGCAUGAUCAACAGAUGUUAGCCCUUUCUGAGCAGAAAAGAAUCAAACACUGGAAGAUGGCAUCUAAACUCAUCCUGCCUGAGUCCCUGAGUUUGUUGACAUUUGAAGAUGUGGCUGUGUAUUUUUCUGAGGAAGAGUGGCAAUUAUUGAAUCCUCUUGAGAAGACUCUCUACAAUGAUGUAAUGCAGGAUAUCUAUGAGACUGUCAUCUCUCUAGGGUUAAAGCUAAAAAAUGACACUGGAAAUGAUCAUCCUAUAUCUGUUUCUACAUCAGAAAUACAAACAUCAGGAUGCGAAGUAUCAAAAAAGACCAGAAUGAAAAUUGCCCAGAAAACAAUGGGCAGGGAAAAUCCUGGUGAUACACACAGUGUACAGAAAUGGCAUCGAGCUUUUCCAAGGAAGAAAAGAAAGAAACCUGCAACUUGUAAACAAGAGCUUCCAAAACUUAUGGAUCUUCAUGGGAAAGGCCCCACAGGGGAGAAACCUUUUAAGUGUCAGGAAUGUGGGAAAAGCUUCAGAGUUAGCUCUGAUCUUAUUAAACACCACAGAAUUCACACUGGAGAGAAACCCUAUAAAUGUCAACAAUGUGACAGGAGGUUUAGAUGGAGUUCAGAUCUUAAUAAGCACUUCAUGACCCAUCAAGGAAUAAAACCAUAUAGAUGCUCAUGGUGUGGGAAAAGCUUUAGUCAUAACACAAAUCUACACACACACCAAAGAAUUCACACAGGAGAGAAGCCCUUUAAAUGUGAUGAAUGUGGAAAAAGAUUCAUUCAGAACUCCCACCUUAUUAAACACCAGAGAACUCACACAGGUGAGCAGCCUUAUACGUGUAGCUUAUGCAAGAGAAACUUUAGUAGGCGAUCGAGCCUUCUUAGACACCAGAAACUCCACAGAAGAAGGGAAGCAUGUCUAGUGUCUCCAAACUGAGGAAAGUUACCAUGUAGAGCUUGACUUUAGAAGUGGUGAAAGAAUACAAAAUUAUGAGGCACCCAAUGAUAGGAAUCUGUGAUUAAUAAAACAUUUGGGAAGGGUACAUGUUACACUUCACAAAAAGGAAUCUAAGCUGUCUGUUUUAUUCAGCAUUGCAUCUUCUGUGCCUAGCACAAGAGUUGAUACAUAAGGAGUACUUUAUAAAUAAAAAAAUGAAAGUGUAGUGAUGAGAUUCCUUUAGCUAUCUAUCUAUAUGUAUAUAUCUGGUUAUUCAAAGCUUCCCCACCCCCAGUCAUCUAAAUUUUUCAGGUAUCAAGUGCUCAACAGACAUAUGAUAGUCAAGGCUCUUAGUCUCAUUUUUUACUCUUUGUCAAGAGAAAUGGAAAAUAAGAGUACUUGGGCCCUCUUAAGGGAGCUCAGAGAGAAUUACUAAAUUAGGGACAGUUUCAAUAGUUAUCAUUCUGUCUACAUGAACAAUCAAGACCAGGACUCAGGGAACUUUACUCUGUAACAGAAAGAGAGGAUUCAGUGUUUGCCCUGGGAGAAUUGUCCCAUUCUUGUUGCUUCUCUCCUGAGUACCCACUACCACAAUGUCUUCUGUCAAGGAAUUACAAGUAGCAAGGGAAGGUCUGAAUGUAAGGACAGGCCUAGGGACCUUGCAAGCACUUGAUAUCUCUCCUCUUGCUGACUUUGUCAACAUAGACAUAUAGUGAAAUGAUGAGGGAGGCAGUCUUGGCCCUCAUCCAGGUAUCUGGUUUUUUUUUGUAGAAAGCACAGAUAAGUGGUAAAUGGUCUUUUUCUGACUUUCAUUAUGUGGACUGGAUGGAGGCUUUCAAACUGGUGCCAUACUGCUGCAGGACCUAAAGGGAGCCCCAUCUUUAUGGCUGAUCAACUACAACCCUAUAUGCCUGAAUACUCUGCAAGAAGGCCUGGAGAUUUUGCAAAACUGAUUUAUUGAGAAUGGCAAGGAGAGCCUUGUGAACUUUUAGCUUUGGUGCACAGCUGAUACCAGGAGGGAACAUCCUGAAGUGUCAGAGAAAAGUAAGGCAUAUGGCUCACAGUGAUGAUGCCAGUCAGAGCCAGGCCAGAUGGAAAUUGUUUUCUGAUGUUACUGGUUUUCUUUUCCCUAUUAGCCAAAGUGACUAUCUCUUAAGAGAAGAUAAUGUGACGUCAAGGGAAGUUGGAAGGCAUGGAUUUAUAUCUAUGUCAGAUCCUGGUUUAUAAUGUUGGCCAAGGCUUAUUUAUAUAUGUUUAUUUAGUAUUCCAUAAAAUUGUACUUCGUAAUGAAAAUGACACAUUUUAUCUUAAAUUUAGACAAUAAACAAAACUUUGUUACCAAAUCA